GAGCCCUCAAAUGCCCGUGUCCCGCCUGCGCUCCGGAGAACCCCUGCCCUGCCUCGGGGACUCGGGAGGUGGGUGUGGGCUCCGAGACUCGGACGGCACCUUGGCGUGGCGAGAGCAGGUGGAGAUGCGCACGGAGGUUGCAUGUUCACCUCCGGGUCUCGGGCGCCACGGCUGCCCGUACCUGUUCCAGCAAGCGUCAGCCAGGAACUGCCGCGCUACUGAUUUUCCCUUCGCUCUUGGGUCCCAACCCCCGGGCUCUCCGGGCUAGGGAGGCGGUGGGGUGGGGUCGAGGCCGUCCCGAGCCACCCGCGGCGGCUUCACACCUGUAUCGGAUUUGCUUUCUCGCCUUUAAUCCUCUCCAAUCCCGAAAGCACCCCAGCAGAGCGCCCCCGCAGCCCGCCUCGAGCCCGGCUCAUACGCAGACGCUGACUGGGGAAGCGAGGGGUCGCCGGUGUGUGAGGCAGGAUUUGAUUUGUAUCCACUGUCACCAGCACUGCUCACUUAGGACUUUCUGGAUCCGGACCCAGGCAGCGCACACUGGACUCUUGAGGAAGAAGGAGACUCUAAUUUUGGAUUCCUUGGUGGAGGAAAAUAAAACACUCUGGUCUUGCCGCCAACGAUGCAAGUGUGACUGCUGGCGUCUUCAUGAGCUCCAGAGGUCACAGCACGCUACCAAGGACUCUCAUGGCCCCUCGGAUGAUUUCCGAGGGAGACAUAGGAGGCAUUGCUCAAAUCACCUCCUCUCUAUUCCUGGGCAGAGGCAGUGUGGCCUCCAAUCGGCACCUCCUCCAGGCUCGUGGCAUCACCUGCAUUGUUAAUGCUACCAUUGAGAUCCCUAAUUUCAACUGGCCCCAAUUUGAGUAUGUUAAAGUGCCUCUGGCUGACAUGCCGCAUGCCCCCAUUGGACUGUACUUUGACACCGUGGCUGACAAGAUCCACAGUGUGAGCAGGAAGCACGGGGCCACCUUGGUGCACUGUGCUGCAGGGGUGAGCCGCUCAGCCACGCUGUGUAUCGCGUACCUGAUGAAAUUCCACAACGUGUGCCUGCUGGAGGCGUACAACUGGGUGAAAGCCCGGCGACCUGUCAUCAGGCCCAACGUAGGCUUCUGGAGGCAACUGAUAGACUACGAGCGCCAGCUCUUUGGGAAGUCGACAGUUAAAAUGGUACAGACACCUUAUGGCAUAGUUCCCGACGUCUAUGAGAAGGAGUCCCGACACCUGAUGCCUUACUGGGGGAUUUAGUGCCACUGAAGCCUGCGUCAGCAGCCCGAGCGGGGCCGGCAUCUGCUCCCCGCCGUCUGCUCCCUCUCCACUCUCUUCUCAAAUGGCUGACUUCUGGUUCUCCCUCAAGUGUUUUUUACACUGGGUGUUCAAAUUUAUUUUAAGAGAUAGGGAGGGAGGGGACAUAAAGGGAAUGCAUACAUUGCUAGUCACAUUUUUAAAAUUAACAUUUUGGAAUAGUGUUUAUGGAAAUCUUUAGCUUUUAAUCAUUUUUACCAAUUUGAACAGUUUAAUAAACUGGUUCUGCUCUCUUCUGAAUCUCAUGCCUUUGGCACCUUGGUAGGUGCAGGAGGAGCUCAGUGCAAAAAUCACUUUGGGGCCUCAUUAACCCUUUAGAGACAAGCUUUGCCCCAGGCUGCGGACCAGACAGAUGCUUAGGGAAGGUUGAUAACCAGCUUCAGUCUCUACUGGAUUAGCCCUACUCUUUCCUUUCCCCUCCAUUAUUUAGUGACUCUGUAAGUAAGUUAAAUACACCCUUAUUAUUUAGCUGUUAAGUAACUAUAAUGAAAUCUGCUGCAAAAUCUCUCUUGGAAUCCAUGUGCCCAGGAUUAUAUUAGCAUUAUUUUUAAUAAAUCUAUAUGCUUAACAUA